GUUGCGGCCCCGCAGCGCCCGCGCGCUCCUCUCCCCGACUCGGAGCCCCUCGGCGGCGCCCGGCCCAGGACCCGCCUAGGAGCGCAGGAGCCCCAGCGCAGAGACCCCAACGCCGAGACCCCCGCCCCGGCCCCGCCGCGCUUCCUCCCGACGCAGGUGAGCCCGCCGGCCCCGGACUGCCCGGCCAGGAACCUGGCGCGGGGAGGGACCGCGAGACCCAGAGCGGUUGCCCGGCCGCGUGGGUCUCGGGGAACCGGGGGGCUGGACCAACACACGUCCUUGGGCCGGGGGGCGGGGGCCGCCUUCUGGAGCGGGCGUUUCUGCGGCCGAGCUCCGGAGCUGGAAUGGGGCGGCCGGGGAAGUGGACGCGAUGGCACCGCCCGGGGUGCGAGUGGGGCCGGGCGCGCGCGGGAGGGGAAAAAGGCGCGGGCGAGCCGCCAGCGCGAGGUUUGUGGUGUCGCCGAUGUCCCUUCGGGGUACUCUAGCGCAGCCGCCUGGCUACUUGACCCACUGCCACCAAACGUUUUAAAUUCACCGAAAGCUUAGCUUCGAAGCAAAGCUCCGUUUCGCCGGUGAAGCAGGAAGCCUUCGCUGCAGGAACUGACCUUUACCUCUUGGAGCGGCUUCUGCAGAAAAAUCCCCGGGCAGAGAUUUGGGCGGAGUUUGCCUAGAACUAACGCGGAGCCAGCCGAUCCCGGCCUACCCCGGGGCCAAGAUUUCAGUGGCUUCCCUUUUUCCUAAACACUUCACGAGGGUCUGUUUCCGGGCUGUGCUCCCCGCCUAGAAGGAAAAUUUUUAGGACCCUUGUUCGCGAAGAGGUGGUGUGCGGCUGAGACCCGCGUCCUCAGGACGGUUCCAUCAGUGCCUCGAUCCUGCCCCACUGGAGGAGGAAGGCAGCCCGAACAGCGCUCACCUAACUAACAGCUGCUGAGAGCUGGGUUCCGUGGCCAUGCACCUGGGACUGCCUUGAGAAGCGUGAGCAAACCGCCCAGAGUAGAAGAUGGAUUGGGGCACGCUGCAGACGAUCCUGGGGGGUGUGAACAAACACUCCACCAGCAUUGGAAAGAUCUGGCUCACCGUCCUCUUCAUUUUUCGCAUUAUGAUCCUCGUUGUGGCUGCAAAGGAGGUGUGGGGAGAUGAGCAGGCCGACUUUGUCUGCAACACCCUGCAGCCAGGCUGCAAGAACGUGUGCUACGAUCACUACUUCCCCAUCUCCCACAUCCGGCUAUGGGCCCUGCAGCUGAUCUUCGUGUCCACGCCAGCGCUCCUAGUGGCCAUGCACGUGGCCUACCGGAGACAUGAGAAGAAGAGGAAGUUCAUCAAGGGGGAGAUAAAGAGUGAAUUUAAGGACAUCGAGGAGAUCAAAACCCAGAAGGUCCGCAUCGAAGGCUCCCUGUGGUGGACCUACACAAGCAGCAUCUUCUUCCGGGUCAUCUUCGAAGCCGCCUUCAUGUACGUCUUCUAUGUCAUGUACGACGGCUUCUCCAUGCAGCGGCUGGUGAAGUGCAACGCCUGGCCUUGUCCCAACACUGUGGACUGCUUUGUGUCCCGGCCCACGGAGAAGACUGUCUUCACAGUGUUCAUGAUUGCAGUGUCUGGAAUUUGCAUCCUGCUGAAUGUCACUGAAUUGUGUUAUUUGCUAAUUAGAUAUUGUUCUGGGAAGUCAAAAAAGCCAGUUUAACGCAUUGCCCAGUUGUUAGAUUAAGAAAUAGACAGCAUGAGAGGGAUGAGGCAACCCGUGCUCAGCUGUCAAGGCUCAGUCGCUAGCAUUUCCCAACACAAAGAUUCUGACCUUAAAUGCAACCAUUUGAAACCCCUGUAGGCCUCAGGUGAAACUCCAGAUGCCACAAUGGAGCUCUGCUCCCCUAAAGCCUCAAAACAAAGGCCUAAUUCUAUGCCUGUCUUAAUUUUCUUUCACUUAAGUUAGUUCCACUGAGACCCCAGGCUGUUAGGGGUUAUUGGUGUAAGGUACUUUCAUAUUUUAAACAGAGGAUAUCGGCAUUUGUUUCUUUCUCUGAGGACAAGAGAAAAAAGCCAGGUUCCACAGAGGACACAGAGAAGGUUUGGGUGUCCUCCUGGGGUUCUUUUUGCCAACUUUCCCCACGUUAAAGGUGAACAUUGGUUCUUUCAUUUGCUUUGGAAGUUUUAAUCUCUAACAGUGGACAAAGUUACCAGUGCCUUAAACUCUGUUACACUUUUUGGAAGUGAAAACUUUGUAGUAUGAUAGGUUAUUUUGAUGUAAAGAUGUUCUGGAUACCAUUAUAUGUUCCCCCUGUUUCAGAGGCUCAGAUUGUAAUAUGUAAAUGGUAUGUCAUUCGCUACUAUGAUUUAAUUUGAAAUAUGGUCUUUUGGUUAUGAAUACUUUGCAGCACAGCUGAGAGGCUGUCUGUUGUAUUCAUUGUGGUCAUAGCACCUAACAACAUUGUAGCCUCAAUCGAGUGAGACAGACUAGAAGUUCCUAGUGAUGGCUUAUGAUAGCAAAUGGCCUCAUGUCAAAUAUUUAGAUGUAAUUUUGUGUAAGAAAUACAGACUGGAUGUACCACCAACUACUACCUGUAAUGACAGGCCUGUCCAACACAUCUCCCUUUUCCAUGACUGUGGUAGCCAGCAUCGGAAAGAACGCUGAUUUAAAGAGGUCGCUUGGGAAUUUUAUUGACACAGUACCAUUUAAUGGGGAGGACAAAAUGGGGCAGGGGAGGGAGAAGUUUCUGUCGUUAAAAACAGAUUUGGAAAGACUGGACUCUAAAGUCUGUUGAUUAAAGAUGAGCUUUGUCUACUUCAAAAGUUUGUUUGCUUACCCCUUCAGCCUCCAAUUUUUUAAGUGAAAAUAUAGCUAAUAACAUGUGAAAAGAAUAGAAGCUAAGGUUUAGAUAAAUAUUGAGCAGAUCUAUAGGAAGAUUGAACCUGAAUAUUGCCAUUAUGCUUGACAUGGUUUCCAAAAAAUGGUACUCCACAUAUUUCAGUGAGGGUAAGUAUUUUCCUGUUGUCAAGAAUAGCAUUGUAAAAGCAUUUUGUAAUAAUAAAGAAUAGCUUUAAUGAUAUGCUUGUAACUAAAAUAAUUUUGUAAUGUAUCAAAUACAUUUAAAACAUUAAAAUAUAAUCUCUAUAAUAA